AGCUGCAGCCCGCCUCUUGCAGCCUGGCGCGACUGCUGUACUGGCCCCUCAGAGAUUUCCCAGCAAGCAGGGUAGAGGGGGACGCAAGGGGACCUGGGGGGCGAUCACCCAGAGCCUAUAUGGCCGGGAAAUCUCCCCGCCUCGGCUACCCCUGACCGGAGCUGGACGCCGUUAUAGACUCGGGUCCUCCCCCACCCCCACUCCAGCACCAUGGAGACUGGUUGCACAGGCCGCCUGGCACGUCAUGGCUGCUUCUGUCCAAACUGCGCGUCCCAAGGCGUUCUGGGGGCGCACGCUGGUUCAGGGAACACUCUGGCUUUGGGAUUCUGCAAUCGGAGAGACUACCUGUAGUCCUGAGGCCUGUAGGCCUGGCUGCUCUGAGGAGGAUUGGCUAUGGCAAAGAAGGACGGCUUUGGCUCCAGGAGAGGGCUGUGAAGGGCAGAGGCCGCACCUGUGUGCUUUGGGCUCUGGUCUGGGCUAGCGAGCUGGCUGGACCGAGGUGGCCUUCAAGGUCCCACACCUACAUACUCCCAGACCACCCUCCAGGCUGGCAGAGGUGGAGCUGUUCAAUGGGCAGCCCAGGGCAAGGGCAGACAGUGGGGCCCAGCUCGCCGUCCUGCCCCCCUUGGAGAGAAACUGAAAGGCUACGUGUGCCGCCUGGCCAUUCAAACUGUCAAUUUUAGGUCCAGAAGUGUCCAAACCACAAGUUCUCAAAACUCUCUGAAAAAUGGCUCCCUCCGAGUUAAGAGCGCCUGGACACCGGAAAAGGCGAUUCCCUGAGCGCCUGGAGUUGGAGACAAUUCCUGGUUCAGAAUUUAAACAUCUUUCUAGGUCUGCGCGGGGCGGCCAUUGGCGGCGGAGUGUCACGUGACCGCGGGGGCGUGCCAAUGUGCGCCCUCACGGGUGUCAAACCCCUGUCAGAGUGUGCGAUCAAGAUCGUGAAACAACGCGAUGCAAAAAGCGACCUACUACGACAGCUCGGCGAUCUACGGUGGCUACCCCUACCAGGCAGCCAACGGGUUCGCUUAUAAUGCCAAUCAGCAGCCGUACCCGGCGUCCGCCGCUUUGGGCGCCGACGGCGAGUACCACCGACCCGCCUGCUCCCUCCAGUCUCCCUCCAGCGCCGGGGGCCACCCCAAGGCACACGAACUGAGUGAGGCGUGCCUGCGCACCCUGAGCGCCCCACCUAGCCAGCCUCCAAGCCUGGGAGAGCCGCCCCUGCACCCGCCGCCGCCCCAGGCCGCGCCCCCUGCCCCACAGCCGCCUCAGCCCGCACCUCAGCCCCCUGCACCUACCCCUGCCGCGCCCCCGCCUCCCUCUUCUGCCUCCCCUCCUCAGAAUGCCAGCAACAACCCUACCCCUGCCAACGCGGCCAAGAGCCCCCUGCUCAACUCACCCACAGUGGCCAAACAAAUCUUCCCCUGGAUGAAAGAGUCUCGACAAAACACAAAGCAGAAAACCAGCAGCUCCAGCUCAGGCGAAAGCUGCGCUGGCGACAAGAGCCCGCCGGGGCAGGCUUCGUCCAAGCGCGCGCGCACGGCCUACACGAGCGCGCAGCUGGUGGAGCUGGAGAAAGAGUUCCACUUCAACCGCUACCUGUGCCGGCCGCGCCGGGUGGAGAUGGCCAAUCUGCUGAACCUCACUGAGCGCCAGAUCAAGAUCUGGUUCCAGAAUCGCCGCAUGAAGUACAAAAAGGAUCAGAAGGGCAAGGGCAUGCUAACGUCAUCGGGGGGCCAGUCUCCAAGUCGCAGCCCCGUGCCCCCCGGAGCCGGUGGCUAUCUGAACUCUAUGCAUUCGCUGGUCAACAGCGUCCCGUAUGAGCCCCAGUCGCCCCCGCCCUUCUCCAAGCCCCCCCAGGGUACCUACGGGCUGCCCCCCGCCUCCUACCCUGCGUCCCUGCCCAGCUGCGCACCCCCGCCACCCCCACAGAAGCGCUACACGGCGGCAGGGGCGGGCGCAGGGGGCACCCCCGACUAUGACCCGCACGCUCAUGGCCUGCAGGGCAACGGCAGCUAUGGGACCCCACACAUACAGGGAAGCCCCGUCUUCGUGGGGGGCAGCUAUGUGGAGCCCAUGAGCAACUCCGGGCCAGCCCUCUUUGGUCUAACUCACCUCCCCCACGCUGCCUCGGGCGCCAUGGACUAUGGGGGUGCCGGGCCGCUGGGCAGCGGCCACCACCACGGGCCGGGGCCUGGGGAGCCGCACCCCACCUACACGGACCUUACCGGCCACCAUCCUUCUCAGGGAAGAAUUCAGGAAGCACCCAAGCUCACCCACCUGUGAUAGUGGGCUUGGGGCUACGCGCCAGGAGAGUCUCCCCCCACCCACCUUUUUUCUUUGGUUGCUUUUUUUUUUUUUUUUUUUUAGGUUCUUCCUGCCCUUUCCUUCCUUCCUUUUCUCUCUUCUCCGCCCCGCACUCCGUUUCCCGGUUUCCCCCCUCGUUGGUAAGGCGUUUUUAUAGUUUAUGUGACGUAGCAAUCUUGGUUGCUGGAAUGGCUGUAUCAUAGCGAUAUUUAUCUCUUCCUGCUCCUCGAUAGGCCACUGGCCCUGCACCCUUUACCUUCUCCACUCUUUGAUCAGAAACAGGGUAUAUGAACAAAUUUUCUAGUCGAGUUUUCAAUGUGAAUUUGUUCUUACAUUAUGGCUCCCGAGGGGAAGCGAUUACUUUUUUUAAUUUUAAAUUUUUUUUUUAAUUGCACUUCUUGUAAAGAGUGAGAAAAAAAAUCAAAGGCGCUUUGAAACAGGGGCUCUCUGUGCAAGGAUGACUAAGUGUACGUCUUUCCGUGUGUGUAUGCUGGUGAACAGUCAGAUUUAUUUAUAUUUUUUUGCAAGCAUUGAAUAAUCUAAGUUUUAAAUAUUAUUUAUCCCCAUCCGUUCGUAUUUAUAUUAAAGAAUUCUGUACCCUGAUGGUUCAGAAGGGUUCUUGGGCCUUUUGUUCAAUUGUGUAUUGGCGUACUUAGAAUUUUUUUUAUUUGAAAGAGAAAUAUAAUUCCUUUAAACGGUAACGAUACAAUAAAACCAGAGAAGAUCCAGCUUUUGAAAACAGUGAUUUAGGUUUGUAACAUCCGGCAAAACUGAAAAAAAAAAUCUGUAAACGCGAAAAAUACUAGAUUUGUUUUGAGAGUUCUUCAUUCCUUGCUGCUCACAUUCUGAGAAACAAAAAGAAAUAAAGUUUUUAUUCUGAAUAA